AUUCCAGGAAGUUUGCAUAGCUCCCUGGACUUCUGCUUUGCACUGCCCUGCAGGAGUGGGUGGGGAAAGGAAGUGGCUUUGAGGCACACAGAGGGGCUUGUUGAGGCCACCGGAGGAAGCUUCUGCCACCAAUAUGGGACCUGUGCCCAGCCUACCAGAAGAGAGCAUCUGAAAACAUGUAUCGACAUGGUAACCCCUCUGCUUGAAGCCUCACAUGGCUCCCUAUUGCCUUGGUGCUGAACACCCUAUGGCUGACCGUGGCCCAGCCUCUGCAACAGCUCUGCCUCCUCUCCAGUGGUGAAGACCCAGCCUGCUGAGACUCCUCCUGCAGUUCCUCAACAUGCCUGCAUUUCUGCUGCCUCAGGGCCUUUGCGAAGGUUGUUCCUUGUAACUGGAAUGCCCUUCCAUCCCUUUUUUAUUCAAAAGGCUGCAAUUUUAAUUGAAGAAAGUUCCCUUCCAAGGUUCAUGAGUUGCCUGACUUGCCCACCGGUUUCCUGCAAGAUCCCUUGGCCUGGCACUUAGUGCUCAGGAAAUAUUUGGUGAUGGGCCAACUGAGUGAGAAGGUGGGAUCUGGUGGGAAGGAAAGCGGAAAGGUAGAAAUUCUGCUCACUUCCUCAUUCCCACCUCCCAAGGAACCCCUGGUGUCCCUGUGGAACCCGCUUUGGGAACCGGUGGUUCAGGUCAGCCUUUUCACUUUGUACUCAAAGCCACAUCGCAUUGAAGCCACAGGUGGGGCAAGGUCAUGCAUGACCUGAGUCUCCAAAUCCCUUCACCCUGUUUGGUUCUGCAACGGGGAUUAGGGGAGCCCCACGAUUUGUUUUCAAAGGAUGUCCGGGCUCCAGGACAGGAUGCCCUGGGUCACCUGAUGACAGGUGUGGUGGUUGGAAAGGGCCUGGUUUCAGCUCCGGGUACACUUCCUCCUUCCUUCUGCUGCGUGGUGUGGCCUCUUCCACGUCCUCAGAAUCCAGCUGUUACUCCGUCCGCGGCCUCUCAGCUCUAGGGCCCUCUGCACACUGGCCCCCCCAGAGCUCUGCGGUAGAAUCCCGUGCCCCCCGACCCCAUCAGCAGCCUACACCCCUUCAUCCUUCCUGGCCCCGGAUUUUCUCUGCCUCUGCCACUCCCGGUGGUAAAAGAGGGCUUAGAAUGCGGUUUGCUUUCUGGCUUUGUUUUUUUGCAUCCUGAUCUUUGUGGCGUGGAUCGAUCAUUUUCCAGGGAAAGUACCUUGGUGUCACGGGCAUCCAGACGGGAUCCAGUGCAUCCUCUUUUAGAAGAAAGGCCUGUCUCCAGAUCCCCGAGUCCCUCUAGCAUCUCCCAGAAGGUGUCAGACGCAGCAGUGUCCAGGGAGCGGCAGCAGCAGAGUCAUGGGUUCAAGCCUCGACUCAGGGGCACUGGGGGGCAUUUAUGAUCGGCUGUGUCUUCUCUCCAGAUUGAGGAAGAGUCUGGGGACACACCAGAAAAGGACAGGAUCAAGAUACUCUGACCCAUGGAUCCCCUGGGCCCGGCCAAGCCACAGUGGUCGUGGCGCUGCUGUCUGACCACGCUGCUGUUUCAGCUGCUGAUGGCUGUGUGUUUCUUCUCCUAUCUGCGUGUGUCUCAAGACGAUCCCACUGUGUACCCUAAUGGGUCCCGCUUCCCAGACAGCACAGGGACCCCCGCCCACUCCAUCCCCCUGAUCCUGCUGUGGACGUGGCCUUUUAACAAACCCAUAGCUCUGCCCCGCUGCUCAGAGAUGGUGCCUGGCACGGCUGACUGCAACAUCACUGCCGACCGCAAGGUGUAUCCACAGGCAGACGCGGUCAUCGUGCACCACCGAGAGGUCAUGUACAACCCCAGUGCCCAGCUCCCACGCUCCCCGAGGCGGCAGGGGCAGCGAUGGAUCUGGUUCAGCAUGGAGUCCCCAAGCCACUGCUGGCAGCUGAAAGCCAUGGACGGAUACUUCAAUCUCACCAUGUCCUACCGCAGCGACUCCGACAUCUUCACGCCCUACGGCUGGCUGGAGCCGUGGUCCGGCCAGCCUGCCCACCCACCGCUCAACCUCUCGGCCAAGACCGAGCUGGUGGCCUGGGCAGUGUCCAACUGGGGGCCAAACUCCGCCAGGGUGCGCUACUACCAGAGCCUGCAGGCCCAUCUCAAGGUGGACGUGUACGGACGCUCCCACAAGCCCCUGCCCCAGGGAACCAUGAUGGAGACGCUGUCCCGGUACAAGUUCUAUCUGGCCUUCGAGAACUCCUUGCACCCCGACUACAUCACCGAGAAGCUGUGGAGGAACGCCCUGGAGGCCUGGGCCGUGCCCGUGGUGCUGGGCCCCAGCAGAAGCAACUACGAGAGGUUCCUGCCACCCGACGCCUUCAUCCACGUGGACGACUUCCAGAGCCCCAAGGACCUGGCCCGGUACCUGCAGGAGCUGGACAAGGACCACGCCCGCUACCUGAGCUACUUUCGCUGGCGGGAGACGCUGCGGCCUCGCUCCUUCAGCUGGGCACUCGCUUUCUGCAAGGCCUGCUGGAAACUGCAGGAGGAAUCCAGGUACCAGACACGCGGCAUAGCGGCUUGGUUCACCUGAGAGGCUGGUGUGGGGCCUGGGCUGCCAGGAACCUCAUUUUCCUGGGGCCUCACCUGAGUGGGGGCCUCAUCUACCUAAGGACUCGUUUGCCUGAAGCUUCACCUGCCUGAGGACUCACCUGCCUGGGACGGUCACCUGUUGCAGCUUCACCUGCCUGGGGAUUCACCUACCUGGGUCCUCACUUUCCUGGGGCCUCACCUGCUGGAGUCUUCGGUGGCCAGGUAUGUCCCUUACCUGGGAUUUCACAUGCUGGCUUCCAGGAGCGUCCCCUGCGGAAGCCUGGCCUGCUGGGGAUGUCUCCUGGGGACUUUGCCUACUGGGGACCUCGGCUGUUGGGGACUUUACCUGCUGGGACCUGCUCCCAGAGACCUUCCACACUGAAUCUCACCUGCUAGGAGCCUCACCUGCUGGGGACCUCACCCUGGAGGGCACUGGGCCCUGGGAACUGGCACCCAUGGGGCCCCACCCAUGAGUGAUGGUUCUGGCUGAUUUGUUUGUGAUGUUGUUAGCCGCCUGUGAGGGGUGCAGAGAGAUAAUCACCGCACCGUUUCCAGAUGUAAUACUGCAAAGAAAACCGAUGAUGAGGCCGGGUGCGGUGGCUCACACCUGUAAUCCCAGCACUUUGGGAGGCCGAGGCAGGCGGAUCACAAGGUCAGGAGAUCGAGACCAUCCUGGCCAAUAUGGUGAAACCCGUCUCUACUAAAAAUACAAAAAUUUGCCGGGCGUGGUGGUGCAUGCCUGUAAUCCCAGCUACUUGGGAAGCUGAGGCAGGAGAAUCGCUUGAACCAGAGAGUCGGAGGUUGCAGUAAGCCGAGAUCGCGCCACUGCACUCCAGCCUGGCGACAGAGCGAGACUCUGUCUCAAAAAAAAAAAAAAAAAAAAAAAAAAUUAGCUGGGUGCGGUGGCCGGUGCCUGUAAUCCCAGCUACCCAGGUGGCUGAGACACAAGAAUCGCUUGAACCCAGGAGGCAGAUGUUGUAGGGAGCCAUGAUCGCACCACUGCACUCCAACCUGGGCGACACAGUGAGACUGUCUCAAGAAAAAAAAAAAAAGGGGGGAGUGUCCCUUUCUGAGUGUGCAA